GUGCAGUAAACUGGAAUGCUCUCCCUCGCUCACUCCUCAGUGUAGGAGUGAUCUGAAGCAGGACAAGCUCAGCCUGCAGCUGCCGUGGGCUUUGUGUGGACUGGACGCAGAGCUUGGGAGACGGGGGAGGGCUAUUACUCCAAUUCACUGUCAAUGGAAUUACAGCUAUAGCGGCAGUGUAUAUAGGAUUGCUUUUUCUCGUCUUCCUGGAGAUGCUCAGUCCCAGUAUAUUUUAAGGAAGAGAAAUAUAAAGGAAAUUUAGUAUGCCUCCUUUUCUUUAAAUGAAGAAUUUAGUUUCCUUUACUUCUUAAAAGAGAAUACCUGUUCUUGUAUAACGUGACUGCACCAGACAUUCUGAAAAAUCAGCAAGAAGCAAAAGCUGGAAAUAGCUAUUUCACAGCAGGUAAUCAUACCUCAGGAUGUAGCUACUGUACAAAGUUUAUACUUGGAUAAUCCUGGAUGGGAAUAAAGGUAGGGGGUAACUGCCUGAAAAACCUAUUACUAUACAGGCCUUAGCAUCAUGAAUGACUUUCUUCAUGAGGAUCUGAAGUUACUAUCUCUGACCACAUUGCACAGAAGAGCCAAUAAGAAUUUCAAAGAGGGCAAUUUCCACUAAGGGAAUUAAGCUACACAAAAGGAACUUUCACACAGAAACUCUAUCAGAAAGAAAAAAAAAAUACAUAGGAAGCCAUGUGUCCUACAUAGUAACAGGAAGCAGAAUUGUUUCUGCCCCCACUUUAAUGAGCUUGCCCACCAUGCUGAACUGCAGCUGGAAUGUUCAUUGACAACAGCAAGCCUGAUCUGGAGGUGUGUACGCCAUAGGAUUACUUGAAUAAACGGUGAAGAACAUUUCCAAGGACUAAACAAAAGUUUAUAAGUCCCAGUCCCUCACCAGGAAAAUAAUAUAUGUGCAUUGGAUAUUCACCCCCGCAAAAUUUACUCACAUCGUUCAAUAAGAAAUCCAUCCAUUUAAAAUAAUGCUUAAAAUUAAUAACCAAAGAAAAUGAAAUGACAUUAAUAAUCAAAGCAAACUAUGGGUUUGAGAUUGAGGAUCUCAAGAUGUGUGUAACUAUUCCUGAGUAUGAAGAGAAUAGGGUUCUGAAGUAACGGAAGCUACCUUGUAUAAAGACCUCAACACUGCUGACCAUGAUCAGCGCAGCCUGGAGCAUCUUCCUCAUCGGGACUAAAAUUGGGCUGUUCCUUCAAGUAGCACCUCUAUCAGUUAUGGCUAAAUCCUGUCCAUCUGUGUGUCGCUGCGAUGCGGGUUUCAUUUACUGUAAUGAUCGCUUUCUGACAUCCAUUCCAACAGGAAUACCAGAGGAUGCUACAACUCUCUACCUUCAGAACAACCAAAUAAAUAAUGCUGGGAUUCCUUCAGAUUUGAAAAACUUGCUGAAAGUAGAAAGAAUAUACCUAUACCACAACAGUUUAGAUGAAUUUCCUACCAACCUCCCAAAGUAUGUAAAAGAGUUACAUUUGCAAGAAAAUAACAUAAGGACUAUCACUUAUGAUUCACUUUCAAAAAUUCCCUAUCUGGAAGAAUUACAUUUAGAUGACAACUCUGUCUCUGCAGUUAGCAUAGAAGAGGGAGCAUUCCGAGACAGCAACUAUCUCCGACUGCUUUUCCUGUCCCGUAAUCACCUUAGCACAAUUCCCUGGGGUUUGCCCAGGACUAUAGAAGAACUACGCUUGGAUGAUAAUCGCAUAUCCACUAUUUCAUCACCAUCUCUUCAAGGUCUCACUAGUCUAAAACGCCUGGUUCUAGAUGGAAACCUGUUGAACAAUCAUGGUUUAGGUGACAAAGUUUUCUUCAACCUAGUUAAUUUGACAGAGCUGUCCCUGGUGCGGAAUUCCCUGACUGCUGCACCAGUAAACCUUCCAGGCACAAACCUGAGGAAGCUUUAUCUUCAAGAUAACCACAUCAAUCGGGUGCCCCCAAAUGCUUUUUCUUAUCUAAGGCAGCUCUAUCGACUGGAUAUGUCCAAUAAUAACCUAAGUAAUUUACCUCAGGGUAUCUUUGAUGAUUUGGACAAUAUAACACAACUGAUUCUUCGCAACAAUCCCUGGUAUUGCGGGUGCAAGAUGAAAUGGGUACGUGACUGGUUACAAUCACUACCUGUGAAGGUCAACGUGCGUGGGCUCAUGUGCCAAGCCCCAGAAAAGGUUCGUGGGAUGGCUAUUAAGGAUCUCAAUGCAGAACUGUUUGAUUGUAAGGACAGUGGGAUUGUAAGCACCAUUCAGAUAACCACUGCAAUACCCAACACAGUGUAUCCUGCCCAAGGACAGUGGCCAGCUCCAGUGACCAAACAGCCAGAUAUUAAGAACCCCAAGCUCACUAAGGAUCACCAAACCACAGGGAGUCCCUCAAGAAAAACAAUUACAAUUACUGUGAAGUCUGUCACCUCUGAUACCAUUCAUAUCUCUUGGAAACUUGCUCUACCUAUGACUGCUUUGAGACUCAGCUGGCUUAAACUGGGCCAUAGCCCGGCAUUUGGAUCUAUAACAGAAACAAUUGUAACAGGGGAACGCAGUGAGUACUUGGUCACAGCCCUGGAGCCUGAUUCACCCUAUAAAGUAUGCAUGGUUCCCAUGGAAACCAGCAACCUCUACCUAUUUGAUGAAACUCCUGUUUGUAUUGAGACUGAAACUGCACCCCUUCGAAUGUACAACCCUACAACCACCCUCAAUCGAGAGCAAGAGAAAGAACCUUACAAAAACCCCAAUUUACCUUUGGCUGCCAUCAUUGGUGGGGCUGUGGCCCUGGUUACCAUUGCCCUUCUUGCUUUAGUGUGUUGGUAUGUUCAUAGGAAUGGAUCGCUCUUCUCAAGGAACUGUGCAUAUAGCAAAGGGAGGAGAAGAAAGGAUGACUAUGCAGAAGCUGGCACUAAGAAGGACAACUCUAUCCUGGAAAUCAGGGAAACUUCUUUUCAGAUGUUACCAAUAAGCAAUGAACCCAUCUCGAAGGAGGAGUUUGUAAUACACACCAUAUUUCCUCCUAAUGGAAUGAAUCUGUACAAAAACAAUCACAGUGAAAGCAGUAGUAACCGAAGCUACAGAGACAGUGGUAUUCCAGACUCAGAUCACUCACACUCAUGAUGCUGAAGGACUCACAGCAGACUUGUGUUUUGGGUUUUUUAAACCUAAGGGAGGUGAUGGUAGGAACCCUGUUCUACUGCAAAACACUGGAAAAAGAGACUGAAAAAAAGCAAUGUACUGUACAUUUGCCAUAUAAUUUAUAUUUAAGAACUUUUUAUUAAAAGUUUCAAAUUUCAGGUUACUGCUGCGAUUGAUGUAGUGGAGAUGCCUGAACACAAUUCUAUAUUUUAGUAUUUUUUAGUAAUUUGUACUGUAUUUUCCUUGCAAAUAUUGGAGUUAUAAACCAUUUACUUUGUGUUCUACUGAGUAAGAUGACUUGUUGACUGUGAAAGUGAAUUUUCUUGCUGUGUCGAACAAUCAGGACUGCAUUCAUAUGAGAUCCUUGUAGUAUAAGCACAGGCCAUUUUUCACUUUGGUAUUAAUAAAAUGUAAAAAAAAAAAACUGGCUGAAUGGCUGAAUGAGAUAAAAUUUAAUUUUAAAAAAUGGUUAUGAAAUAAUGUUCCAAUUAUUAAAUUUGUAUUAUCCCAGUGGUAUUCAAUAAAUCAAAAUGUGUGAAGUAAUGGGCAAUAUCAAACUUCCUGCAUAUCUCCAUUUUUGCUCUAGGCAAAUUAAUUAUCCUUAAAAAAGUUAAGCAUAUCUUCUGAACUGAAUACAUCAGCUGGCAUAAAAGGAGCAUGAAGUCUGUUAAAGCCAUUGUCAGCAAAGCUUUGAAAAUAAAGGACUUCACAAAAACGGUAAUGUAAAUGUGCUUCCAAGUUGGGGGGAAAAUGUGUACUUAGGAAAACAUGGAAACUUAGACUUGUAUAGUGUAAUGAACACAAAUACCAAAACUGCAUUUUGGUUUUGCCUAUACCAUCCUGAUUUUUGAAAAGUGAAUUAUAAACACAAAAUUGUUAGUGUUUAUGAUGUUUUUAUCAUAAAGGAUGUCAGAGAAACUUUAUGCAUAUUAAAAAUGUAAUGUAAUUAUAAGCGAUUCCCCUCAACAAUCCAGAGAAAGUAGUUCUUUAAAUAAGAGAUAAUUUAAAGAAAAAUAAAUACUAGACAUCAAAUUUAGAUCUGGUUUAUGUCAAAGGUUUUAACACUGUACAUAAAUGUUCAAUUUACUUUUACAAAGAUCAAGAAUACUGCCCAUUACUGUCACAAUUUUCCAGAUAUUAUAUAAUGAACUCGUAAUGUAACAUUUCCUUCUAGCUUCCUACUGAAUUGUGAGCUGUUACUUGUUGAAAAACCAUAUCACUUUUCUGUUGCCAUGAUUUUUUUUUUUUCAACAAAAAACCAAAGUGCAUUGUACGCCCUUUGGCCAGUCUUGUAUGUGCCUUGAUCCAACGCUACAUGUAUUCAGCUUUUAAAACUCCACAAAUUUUUCAUACUCCUUAAAUAUGAAAAAUUAUGGUCUUAUUGCUGAAUAAAACUUUUAAAAAGUACAGAAUAAUUGUGCUUGCUUUUUCAGGAUUGUGUUACUAUCACUAAGUAGCAAAUUGCCCAGCACAUUAGUCCUAAACGUCCCAUGUAUUUUUCUAGGCAUAAAAAUAAAAGUUGGCUAAAAAUUUUAAAAAAUCAACAUCUUGAGGUUGUGUAUCAUUUUACUUCAAAGAGUUCAGUGUUUCAUGUAUAAAUGUAUUUCCUCUUACUUAUACACUGUAUAGAUGGAAAAUUUAAGAAAUGGUUUCAAAGCCUUUCUCUCUUAGGCGCACUGCUGCCACUGUCCUGAUACUUUUUAAGGUGGUCUUUGAAAAACUGUUUUUUUAAAAUAGCCUUUUAGUAGAGUGAGUUGGCAUUUGUGAUACUGUGAAAUACACACUUUCUCUUUGUCCCUGUUUCUGGCAUACAACUCCUAAAAUCCUUGCAAUCUUCAAAGUGAUAUAUUUUCAUAUGCUAAUGAGUUCACUGAUAGCUGGCAGGCCCUAGGUAGCUUCAAGAUAAAGUCUGAUCAUUGAAAAGACCAAGACAUGAUUAUAGGGUUGGGACUUACAACCCCAAACCCUAACCUCCAGAGAGGGCGAAGUGGAUGAAGAUUAAGUUGAUCACCAGUGACCAGUGGUUUAAUCAAGCAUGCCUAUGUAAUCAAGCCUCCAUAAAAAAACAAAAGGUCAAGAUUUGGAGAGCUUCCAGAUUGCUGAACAUGUGGUGGUUCCUGCAGGAUGGCAUGCCUGGAGAGGGCAUGGAAGCUCUGUGCCCACCUAGACCUCACCUUAUGUUUCCUGCCAUCUGGAUCCUUUGUAACAUCCUUUAUAAUACGUCAGUAAAUCUGUUUCCUUGCAUUUUGUGAGCUGUUGUAGCAAAUUAAUAGAACACAAAAAGGGGAUCCUGGGAAACCAAACUUGAAGCUGACUAGUCUUGCAACUGGUGUCUGAAGAGGAGGCAGUUUUGUGGGAAUAAGCCCUCAACCUGUGGGAUAUGACACAAUUUCCAGGUAGACAGUGUUGGGAUUAAACUGAAUUGGAGGACACCCAGCUGGUAUCUGCUGAAGAACUGAUUGCUUGCGUGGUGUAUGGGGCAAAACUUGUUAAGACAAGUCUUCUAUGUUGAUUAUUGUUGAAUGAGAGAAUUAAACACACAUACACACUUUGA